AGCCGAGAGGUGUCACCCCCAGCGGGCGCGGGCCGGAGCACGGGCACCCAGCAUGGGGGUACUGCUCACACAGAGGACGCUGCUCAGUAAGUACUUCCUUCCUCCCCGCCAGAACCCGCCUGCUGGGUCUGCCCACGGGUGCCGGUGGGGAGCAGAGGCACCCUCUGCCCUCCGGGAACUGGGGAGGCCAGGCGCCAGGCAGAAGGAUGCUGAGAAGGGGAGAGAGCCAGGAGGUCAGGCAGAGAGAGUGGUCCACUGAGAACCUGGCAUCUCCACAGGUAGAGAAGGGGCAUCCCUGGAAGGCUUCCAGGGGGAGGUGAUGUCAAGAUGUAGAGGCAACUCUGGGAACCAGGGGGUGAGAGAAUAGGAUGGGCAAAGAGGCUGGGCAGGAGAGGGAGGCUCAGAAGCUGGGCAGGGAAGUGGUGUGAGGUGUGGAGGGGUUGUGGGGCCUCCAGCUUGCCCGGGAUGAAUAGAAAGUCAGCCAGGCCUGGGGGCCCCAGGGCCCACACAAUCACACAGCAUGCACAGCCACACCCACAUGGCCACAUGCGCACACAGCCAUAUGACGUCAUCUACAGCCCUGGAUCUCACCAGCCCAGGAACCCCCACAUGCAGACCAGAGUCCCCAUGGUGAACGGAACAGGUCUCCCUCACGCCGCACACAGACCCAGAUGCACAGCCACACAGAAACCCCAGUCCCACGUGCGCUGCCACAGGCACAGGCCCCUGCCAGAGCCCGGCAGCAGAUACCUGGGGAGGCGGCGAGGGUGCCGUGGGGUCGCUAAGCCUGGGUGCCUGGCCCCUUGGCCCUCCCCAACAGCCAGUCUUCCCCAAAGGGCCGGAUGGUUCUUAGGACGGGAACGAUGGUGUCACUGCCUUCCGGGCCAUUGCGCCAUAGGCCCCUUCCGACCACGUGGCUGCCGGUGCCCCGUUGGGGGUGGUGGUGAGCGGUAACUGUACCCGCCCCCAACACCUUCUGACAGGCUCACAGCAUCCCUGGUGGGCCUGACAGAAGGAGCCACUUAUGGAGAGAGGAGGGAGGCAAGAGAGGUCAGGGGAGAGCCCUGGCCUUGUGUGACCUGAGUAGGACCUUCUCCUGAGACUUGGUUUACCUGUCAGGAAAGUGGGGACAUGGACUGGAAGGUCUUCCACAUCUGUUCCAGGCUGCACCUCUGGUUGAAAAGGCAGCCUCUCCUGGUUCUAGACAGAGCUGAGGACACAAGCUGCUCCCGGGCUGCCUGCCCUGAAGCCCUCUCAGGCCCAUCUACCUGGAUGGCCAGAGCAGCUGACAAGGCAGGUCCUAGGGCAGUGGCCGGUCUUUAGCCCAGUGGUCUUGCAGGGAGCCAGUCCCACCUUGCAGAGAGUCAGCUCCCGAGGUUAGAACCGUGCUGUAGGCAGGACUGGGAUCCGGCCAGGCACUGCAGCCUUUGCUCAAAGACCUACUUGGUCUGGUCCUUGCACUCCUGUUUCCAAGCAUGGCGAGCAUGGCGGCUAUAGGCAGCUGCUCGAAAGAGUACCGCGUGCUCCUUGGCCAGCUCCAGAAGCAGACAGAUCUCAUGCAGGACACCAGCAGACUCCUGGACCCCUAUAUACGUAUCCAAGGCCUGGAUGUUCCUAAACUGAGAGAGCACUGCAGGGAGCGCCCCGGGGCCUUCCCCAGUGAGGAGACCCUGAGGGGGCUGGGCAGGCGGGGCUUCCUGCAGACCCUCAAUGCCACACUGGGCUGCGUCCUGCACAGACUGGCCGACUUAGAGCAGCGCCUCCCCAAGGCCCAGGAUUUGGAGAGGUCUGGGCUGAACAUCGAGGACUUGGAGAAGCUGCAGAUGGCGAGGCCGAACAUCCUCGGGCUCAGGAACAACAUCUACUGCAUGGCCCAGCUGCUGGACAACUCAGACACGGCUGAGCCCACGAAGGCUGGCCGGGGGGCCUCUCAGCCGCCCACCCCCACCCCUGCCUCGGAUGCUUUUCAGCGCAAGCUGGAGGGCUGCAGGUUCCUGCAUGGCUACCAUCGCUUCAUGCACUCAGUGGGGCGGGUCUUCAGCAAGUGGGGGGAGAGCCCGAACCGGAGCCGGAGACACAGCCCCCACCAGGCCCUGAGGAAGGGGGUGCGCAGGACCAGACCCUCCAGGAAAGGCAAGAGACUCAUGACCAGGGGACAGCUGCCCCGGUAGCCUCGAGAGCACCCCUUGCCGGUGAAGGAUGCGGCAGGUGCUCUGUGGAUGAGAGGAACCAUCGCAGGAUGACAGCUCCCGGGUCCCCAAACCUGUUCCCCUCUGCUACUAGCCACUGAGAAGUGCACUUUAAGAGGUGGGAGCUGGGCAGACCCCUCUACCUCCUCCAGGCUGGGAGACAGAGUCAGGCUGUUGCGCUCCCACCUCAGCCCCAAGUUCCCCAGGCCCAGUGGGGUGGCCGGGCGGGCCACGCGGGACCGACUUUCCAUUGAUUCAGGGGUCUGAUGACACAGGCUGACUCAUGGCCGGGCUGACUGCCCCCCUGCCUUGCUCCCCGAGGCCUGCCGGUCCUUCCCUCUCAUGACUUGCAGGGCCGUUGCCCCCAGACUUCCUCCUUUCCGUGUUUCUGAAGGGGAGGUCACAGCCUGAGCUGGCCUCCUAUGCCUCAUCAUGUCCCAAACCAGACACCUGGAUGUCUGGGUGACCUCACUUUAGGCAGCUGUAACAGCGGCAGGGUGUCCCAGGAGCCCUGAUCCGGGGGUCCAGGGAAUGGAGCUCAGGUCCCAGGCCAGCCCCGAAGUCGCCACGUGGCCUGGGGCAGGUCACUUUACCUCUGUGGACCUGUUUUCUCUUUGUGAAGCUAGGGAGUUAGAGGCUGUACAAGGCCCCCACUGCCUGUCGGUUGCUUGGAUUCCCUGACGUAAGGUGGAUAUUAAAAAUCUGUAAAUCAGGACAGGUGGUGCAAAUGGCGCUGGGAGGUGUACACGGAGGUCUCUGUAAAAGCAGACCCACCUCCCAGCGCCGGGAAGCCCGUCUUGGGUCCUCGCUGCUGGCUGCUCCCCCUGGUGGUGGAUCCUGGAAUUUUCUCACGCAGGAGCCAUUGCUCUCCUAGAGGGGGUCUCAGAAACUGCGAGGCCAGUUCCUUGGAGGGACAUGACUAAUUUAUCGAUUUUUAUCAAUUUUUAUCAGUUUUAUAUUUAUAAGCCUUAUUUAUGAUGUAUAUUUAAUGUUAAUAUUGUGCAAACUUAUAUUUAAAACUUGCCUGGUUUCUAAA